AGUCUGAGAUGCGCGGAUGCUUCAGCAUGCCUCCAGAAGCAGAGAAAGAACAAAAGCACUGGAACCGGUCUCCGGUUGCCUCUAGACUCAGAGAAGCUGGGUCUAAGUGUAGUGUUAGCUGCAGAUACCUGCUCAGCUGGCUAAGCCUUUAACAUGGAAAGAAGGCUCAUAAAGAAGGAAAUGAAAAAGCUCUUGGGAGAUUAUAUUGGCAUCAGACUUCGGGAAAAUGAAUUUGACCCAAAAGGAAGACGGCAACUCACCUUUCUAGAUGAUAUGGCACACUAUGACUUGGCCAUCAGUGUUGCUUUGCAAUGGCUGGAUCCCUCAGAAGACUUAACUUGGCUGGAGUGGGAGGAACUGAAAAUACCACUCCAUGGCAGACCCAUAUAUCCAAAUCGUAGAGAACGAGAAGCUAUGAUUUUAUCAUCUUAUGCUGGAAUCUUAAUGAACAGUAUCCCGAUUGAGGAAGUCUUUAAAAUUUAUGGGGCUGAUUCUUCUGCCGAUUCUGGUACCAUCAAGGUUCCCCGAGUUUCAUCUCUCUGCCUCUCCUUGCACCCCUUUGCCAUGUUAACAGCACCCAAAGCAGCAGCAUACGCCCGCAAACAGAGUGUCAAGUCAAGAAAGGUAACAACAAAUAAAAAUGCCACCAGCAUCUCUGCAAAGGAAGCAAAUGCCACAGAAUGGAAAUCAUCACAAAGGUUUUCAGACACACAGCCAAAGCACAAAGUCACUUAGAAAAUUGGAAUUGUACCAUGGAACUUCAUAAUAGAUUCUCUGGGAGCAGACGAGAAGCAUCAUCUUAAAACCACAGCUCUUGCCAGUACAUUUUUCUUUACAACUGUUUUUGGUACAACUGCACUGAAGUGUUAUUUUUGAUGUUGAGCUUUCUUCUUUUAGAAGCAUAUUGCAUGGCUACAUUUUCUUAAAAAAAAAAACUGUGACCUUAUGCUACUUCAUUGUGACUGGAAGACUGCUGGAGAAUUCAGAAAGUAUAUAGUAUUUCUGUGUUAGAGCAAGCUGGCUUUGUAGCACAUUUUACAAAUGUGUGGCAUUGAAUAUUGCACAGUGAUGGAGUGGGAGGCAGAUUUCCAAAGAGUUAAUCCAAAAUAAAAUUAAUCUGUCAUUGAUUGCCUUUACUGUGUUCUCAUAUGAAAAGAAUGUUUAAAUCAUUUCAAUAAAGCAUUAAAAAAAUGAA